GAAAUUUUCCAGCAGAUAAAUUUGGUCAUCUGGAGAGGCAUCCAUUUAUAUACAGCAGUUUGUGACAGUCUGAGAUUAUACUUAAUAUACACACUUGUGCUUAAAAUACCUUUUUGAAGACAGGAAUGUAUGGCUCCUAUUAGAUAAGAUUUCCAUCAAAAACAAUUUCAAUAGUUCAGUGUUAAUCUUUAGACAAGGUAUUUUUACCCAGCGCUCUGGGUAGCUGAUUAUUUGGUGCUGUUUAUGGUGGCACUUACAGUGAUUUUUGUGGUACACAUUGUUCUGACCAUAUCAAUAAUAUGCUAGAUGGUUGAAGCAGCUGGGUUAGCAUGCUUUGAAAGUCAGAUGAAUUCUUACUGGUAGAUUUUUACUGUAUCUGUAUGUUACUUGUUUAAAGUUUGUUGUGAUGUGUAUAAUAAUGGUGUUUGUUUUUAAAGCUUAAUUUUGGUUUUCAGUAAUGUAUUACCAUCCCUCAGACAAUAGUCAUUUUUGUUUGUUGACAUUGCUUUUAAAGUUAAAAAAGAAAAGUGACAUAUUUAGGAAAUAACAUUAUUGCCAAAUAUCACAGACUGGCAGAAAAUGUAAGCAAAUACCAGUGCAGAGAAUUUCAGUAGGAUUUUAGUGAUUUUAUAUAUUUGCAGCAGAAUUACUGCAUUUUAGAGCUAGAAGGAACUGCUCUGAUUAUAGAUUAUCUUCGUCCUUGCACAGAUGAGGAAAUUGGGUCUAAGCAGGGUGUCAUCUGCCCAGAGUCACACACCACAUUAGUAGUCGAUUUCAGAGUGGACUCUGGUGUAUGCAGCCCUUCUUGCUGUUGAUGCUUAAGGUUUUAAUUUAAUCCUGGGAACUGGGGAGUUUGGAUUCGUGUCUUCCUGGAGGAUGUUACAGUUGAGCUGGCUCUUGCAGGGUGACGUGUGUUUGAUUGGAGAAAGAUACAGAAGGCAGGAACAGUAUCUAAAACAGGACGAAUCACAGGAGCCUCUACCGUCAACUUAGAAAUUCUUUUCUCCUUCCCAAGUGGGGUUCCUUGUUUUCAGUUCCUUAGUUUACCGCCUUGAUAUGAUGAAGCUCAUCCUCAUAGUGACUUCCUGUGAAAGGUGAUGGGGAAGAUGACUUUUUUUUUGAGCCUUGUGUGUCAGAAAAUGUCUAUGUUCUAAGUAUUUGGUGUAUGCCUGGCUGUGUAUAAAAUUUCAGGUUAAUAUUUUAGUUCAGAUCAAAUAAGUUAUUUGGCAGUGACAAAUUAACUCUGAAAUCUCAGUGCAUGAAUAGAGGUCUGUGUCUUGCUUUCACAAAGUCUGCUGUGGACGCCGCCUCCCUUGGCCUCUUCCUUUGGGUCCAAUCUGCUUUCACCUACAGUUCCUGUCUGUUGUCCCCAUGGCGGAUGUGGGUGUAUCUGCAGGUCGCACGCUGGUCACCAUAGGCCAGAACCAGGCCUAGUCCCUGCAAGAAUUCCAGACGCAUGCAAGGGCACAAGGAGAGUCAUUGAACUGUCAGUGGGGGUCAUAGUUGUAAGUGUGUUUCCUCUUGGAAUAUUGCAGGCAUUGCUCCGUUGUCGUCCGGUUUUCAGUGUUACUGUUAAGUCACAUGCCGCCAGUUUCCCAGGCAGUUGUAAGCCAUUUCUUUUCCCCCUGGAAGCUUUUGGGGGACUUUUGUGUUAUUGCCUAAAUACUAACAUUUUACCAUGGUGGGUCUGGUGAUUGUUCUUUUCUACUUUGGAUGUGCUGAGCAUUCCACAGAGCUUUUCAGUCUAUAAACUUAUGUUUUUCAGUUCUAGAAAAACUAUUAAAAUGACUUUUAUAAUUUCUUCCCUUUCAUUUUCUCAUUUUCUUUCUUUUUUUUUUUUCUGUCUUAAGCUCUUCUUCAUUGGACAUAGGAACUCCUAAAUCCGUCUACUUAUUUUCUUAGCUUUUUUCUCCAUUUUUCUUGUCUGUUGUUGUUGUUGUUGUUGUUGUUCUUUGGAGGGGAGUUCCCUCAAUUUUUCUUUUAUUGAAUGUUUACUUUUUGGCUGUGGGAGUUUUGUUUUCUAACUGUUCUCCUCACCCCCUCUUUUUUAAACAAAUAGCAUCCGCCUCUCAGUUCAGAUUUGUGAAACCUUUUCUCAGGCUGGUUUUUCGUCGUCUUCCUUUCCAGCAGUCUUAGAUUUUGGUUUACUCCAGUUUGUUUUAGCCACUUAACACUGUUGUCAUCUGCCGUAAUUCGCUUUGUGAUUUUCUUCGUUCCUGUGUUUUUGGGGAAUGAUGGAGAUAAAGAAGUGUAUGUUUAAUCAGGAGGGUUUUUUUUUCCCUUCUUUUCAACAGUUUUUGUUUGUUUUGCUAGCAUCAGUGAAUAUUAAACCCUUCGUUUUUGGGAAAACCAGAUCUAUUUUUUUCUUUAAAUAAAAGUAGUGUUUUCAGUUAGUGCUCUCAUGAAGCCACAUCUGUGUCACUGAGUUCAAUUAACUUAGUCGAUGAAAUGCCUGCUGAUCUGUAGUGGGUGGUAACAUAAUUAUUUUAAUUUGGACUAUUUUAAAAGCAUCAAGAGAUCGCAUCUUUGGGAACCCACAAUAAAUGGUUACUUUUGGCAAUCAGAUUAUUGUUUUAUAAUACAAGUAAUCUUUUCAUUUUGUAAGAUUUUUAUAUUGUUUGCUUAAUAGGGAUAUAUUAUUAAAUUGAAUAAUUAUUGCUUUCCAAGAUUCCCUUCAGCGCUAAUGAUCAAUGAAUGAAGUUUAUGUUGGCUCUUAAUGUACAUUUAAUAACAAAUUUCAUGUGGAUUACUUUUUGUUCCCCAAAUCUGCUAUUUAAAACUCCAUUCUUCAUUUGGAUGUACUUUAGAAAUGGGGAAAAGAUUAUUUUAACUGAAAACUCAAAUUCUCUACUGCAAAUUGAAUGACAAAAUCUUGUAUGUUCUAUGUGAAAGCAUUUGAAUAAUGGGCAAAUUGCUCUUUAAAUUAGAGCUUUUGUGUUGAUCUGAAGGCUCUGAGAGCAGUCAUAACAGUUGUGUUAUUUUUCAGUUAGUUUUACAUGCAUGUUGCCUUUCACAAGUUAGAUAUUUUUGCUUUAGUAGUUCAUUACAUUUAAGAUAUUUUAAUAUAUAAACAAAUUACUUUUAAUCUUAAAGCAAUGAAGAAACUAUUAAAACACUUUGCUACAGUACAGAAUAAAAACAAAACAUCUUUGUUCAUAAUUUGUCAAAUUCUGAAAGAAUCUUACCUACUUGGUAGUUUAUAAUUCAUGAGGUCAUUCUUUUUCAUAGACAAUUAAUGUGGUGAGAUUUUUAGGGAAUUUGCUAUAUUUUUAGUUAAAAUAAUUUUGUUUACAUUAAAAUGUUAAAUAAUUGUUUUUUAAUUUGUCAUUGUCAGCUAUAAUCAUAUAUAGGUGAAUGGUAUUAAAAGAACUAUAUAUAAGAUAGUAUUUUACAUUUAUCAUUCUGGAGGUCAGGAUGUAUUAUAUAUAUAUCAGAAAGUAUUACAAUAGCUGUUUCUAAGCCACCAACUGUAAUUAUACCUUAGCCAAUAAGGUUGCAGAUGUGGACAUCAUUAAGGAUCUUACUAGUAGUAAGUUGGGGUGCUGUCUUUUCAGUGUGCAAAUGAUUUCCAUUAUCAAUGUUGCCCAGGUCUCCACUGAUUUAGAGUUAAGAUACCUAUAUUAAUUUGUUGAAAAGUGUCAUAGUUAUUUCAUAGGAGUCUCAGGCCUGAUACACACAGUGGUAAAGAUAAAAGGCUGAUUUAUUUCUUGUGAUGUGUUUCCAACACCAACAACCACUUCUUCAGUGUGAAAACUGAGUGUCCAGGCUGGGUGCGGUGGCUCACACCUGUAAUCCCAACACUUUGGGAGGCCGAGGUGGGCGGAUCACUUGAGGUCAGGAGUUCGAGACCAGCCUGACCAACGUGGCAAAACCCCGUGUCUACUAAAAAUACAAAAAUUAGCCAGGCACGGUGGCACAUGCUGUAAUCCCAGCUACUUGGGAGGCUGGAAGGAGAAUCGCUUGAACCCGGGAGGUGGAGCUUACAGCGAGCCAAGAUCAUGCCAUUGCACUCCAGCCUGGGCAACAAGAGCGACCCUCCGUCUUAAAAACAAAAAAAGAAAACUGAGUCCAACAUUUCAGUUAAUUCAGACCCUACCCAGAGUAAGUACAGUCCCCACAGGCAACGGGCUGAGUCCCAUGAGACUGCCCCGUCCUCAGAUGCCAGUCACAAGUCCCAGGCCUCUCAUACUUCUGACCGACUGGCUACAAAUCAGGGGUUCCCACUACCUCCUCAGAUUAGAUAAUUUGCUGGAUAAAACUCAGGAAAACAUUAUUAUUAAGGGCACAACUCAGCAACAGCCCAGUAGAAGAGGUGCACGGAGCAAGCACGGGGGGACGUGGAGUUUCUGUGCCCUCCUAGGGUGGCCUCCUGCCCAGCUCACCCUUGUGUGUGCAAGGUCCCCGAAUCUUGUAGUUAGAGUUUCUGUAGAACUCAAUCUCUAAUCCUUUCCUUUUCUCUUCAUUUCUCUUCAGGAUAGGGACGGGGGGUCGGUGCUGAAAGUUCCACACUCUAGGCACUGGGUCUCUGGGUGACCAGCCCCAUCCAGAGGCCAUCUAGGAGGGCCGCUUUUAAUCACAGCGUUAGCAUUAACAGUUGUGAUUGAAAGGGGCUUGUUUUGAACAAUAAAAAAUAUUUCUAUCUCAGGAAAUCCCAAAGAUAUAGGAACUGUGCCAGGAACUAGAGACAAAGAUGAAAUAUGUCUUAUAUCACAUUUCUUUGAAUUGGUUAAGUGCAAAUAAGACAACAAAAAAUAAUAUAACCAUUUAUAUAACACUUGUGUUAGGUGUUAUAAAUAAUCUAGAGAUGAUUUAAAGUAUGGGGAGGAUGUACAUAGGUUAUAUGCAAAUACUAUGACGUUUUAUAUAAGGGACUUGAGCAUUCAUAGCUUCUGUUAUUCCUGGAGCCAAUCCCCCAUGAAUACCGAGGGAUGACCGUAUACGUAUAAAGACAGUGAUGAAUUGGCAUAUAUAUUUACUACUUCUUAAAUGCAACUUGUUAAAAUCUGAACUAAAAAAUUAAGGAGAGGUGUGCAGUCAUUUAAUCAAUUCUUUAUUUUUUUUUUUCCUUAAGACUUAGUCUCUCUCUCGCCCAAGCUGGAGUGCAGUGGCAUGAUCUUGACUCACUGCAACCUCUGUCUCCUGGGUUCAGGUGAUUCUCCUGCCUCAGACUCCCAAGUAGCUGGGAUUACAGGCACCCACCACCACACCUGGUUAGUUUUUGUAUUUUUUUAGUAGAGACAAAGUUUCACCACGUGGGCCAGGCUAGUCUCGAACACCUGACCUCAAGUGAUCUGCCAGCCUCAGCCUCCCAAAGUGCUGGGAUUACAGGUGUGAGCCACCGCGCCCAGCCUCAUUAAUCAAUUCUUAUAAGCCAACACAAAAAGCAUUUUUACAUGAUUGACGUUAUGAAUAUUUGUUUCAUAUUCAGUUUAAUAAUUGAAUAAGAAUGCAUUGAAUACAAUUACAGUGAAGGAUGCUUAGAAAUGCUCAUGGGAAAGUUGUUCAUUGCUGGUUAGAUAUCUAAGUCCGUACAUAUUUUUAUUUUCAUUGAGUCAGAAGCUUUUAGAACUGGACAUGAUUUAGAGAUUAUCAUGUAUUUUAUAUGGAGAUUCACUUAGUAUCCCCCUGCAAAUUUAAGCUAGUGCUACCCCAUACUUUUGUGUCAAUAGCCUAUAAAGUAGGAGUGAAUCACUUGAAAAUUUAUUAGAACUUUUGUUGUAAAUAUAAAUUUAUUCUUAAUUUAAGUUAAAAUUAUUUGUCAACUUUAAGUUCAUUUUUCUCAAUUUGGCUAUAUUUAACUUUUUUAAAUCUACCUUUGUAGCCAUGCAGUGUUCCUGUUGCAUUUCAAUUAGAGGUUAUUGUGGUAAGAGCUAAGGGCCCUGAAAGAAGUCAAAGCAACUGUAUUCCAUUUAUUAUGCAAAUGUAAUUCUGUUUUUAUGUAGUUGUAAAUAUUUAUUAUGUUUGAAUGCAGUUGCCGAGAAGUGUGAAAUGUCUGAGAUUUUUGCCUUCAACACAAGCUCAAAGGCAGGCUCACCAGUUAGCCAGCUACCAGUUGGAUGCUGGCAGAAGACAUAAGACUCUUGGGUUAGAGAUAAAGGACCUUAUUACAGUAGUAGCCACAGUGUCAGCAUCUGUCCCAGUUUGCUGAGACAUGUUGAGAAUAGAAUGGGGCAGGGGAAAGAAAGCAAGGAAACUUAUUAGGAGGUAUUGCCAUAAUGCAGGAGAAAGAGGAUGGUAGCUUGGACUAGUAUAGUGGCAAAAAGUAGUUGGAUUCUGCAUAUGUUUUGGAGGUAGCUGAAAUUGGGAUUUCAUGACAUACUGGAUGAGGAAUGAGAGAAAGAAAGGAGCCAAGGGUGAUUCUGAAUGUUCUGAUCUGAUCAUUGGAAGAAUGUAGAGUAGCCGGAAAUGGAAGUAUAGAGAAGAUUUAAACCUGCAAGUGGGGCUGGGGUGGGGGUGGGGUGGGGAACAACCCGAGUUUAGUUUUGAACUUGUGAAGUUUCAGAUAUCUGCAAGACAUCAAAGUGGCAGUGUCCUGAAGGGAGCUGAAUAUAACUGGUCUGUAAAUGAAGAGAGAGAAUUUGGGAGUGUAGGGCACAUCGAUGCUAUGCAGUGUCAUGAGCAUGAGUGAAAUCACAGGUGGAGAAGAGGGGACCAAAGUCUUGAGUGCUGGGGCACUCCUGUUAAGACUCCAGAGGGAGACUAGCAAAGGAGUCAGACUGAGGGACCGUGAGAGUGUGGUGUGCUGAGCAAAGAGGUAAAAUGAUAUGAAAGGAAAAGGAGUGGUCAGUGGUCACACACAGUGCCUCUAAGAUUAGGACUGUGAAUUCACGCUAGGCAAAGGCUGCUCUGUGCGAUGAUUGGUAGAGAAGGCUUUGGUGUGGGUGUCAGAGAAGAUUGGAGAGGAAUCGUGGGCAUCAGUAGACUCAGUUCUCCUAAGGCAUUUUGCUGCAAAGGGAAUCAGAGAGAUGGGGCUGCAGCUGGUGAGGAAGGUGGGGUCCCCACAAGUUUGUUUAUAUAUGAGAAAUAACAUUUUCAGGAAUGAGCCAGUGGAGUGGGGAAAUUGUUGGGAGAUUAAGUGUGCCAGCUGACGGUGGGGGCCCUUGAGCAAGGUAGCAGAAUGGAGUAGAUGGAAACAUGGUGCUGAGUGGGUAGAUGGGAGCCGAGUCCAAGGUCUUCUGAUGUCGUUCCUUUUCUUGGUGAAAUAGGAAGUUGGGCCAUCUGCUGCGAUAUUAAAUGAGGGAGUGUUCCAGGGGUAAUGAGAGUGUUCCAGGGGUGGAGAAAAGAGAGGGAAGGUGUGAAAUGGUAGGCCGGGAAGGAGAAGAAUGGACCAGGGAAAAGUAGUUUGAUUUCCAGACAGCAUUAAGGACCCACCUGCGGGUCAUGGCCUUGACUACAAAGUGAGACCCAUCAGACCAGUUCUCUUUUUCUCCAGCCUUAUUUAGCUCUAUGGGUGCAGGCAUGACAUAAGCGGAGUUGAAUUUACUAAUAUGGUUUUACCAAGAGAGUUUUUCAGGAGAGUAGUGGAAGGGAAUAGAAGUAUACACAAGGAAAUGAUUACAGUGAUGAAUUGUGGAAUAUAAGCUGAGUAGGAAGGGAAGAGGGUCUUGAAAAGCUGGUAGGCUUAUCACUCUUGUCAUUUAGACUUUGAAUAUUCAAAGCCGGUUCCUAACUGUAUAUAUAUAUACACCAGUAUAAAAAAAAAAUUUAAGUCAGAUUUGCAAAAAGUUAUUUUGAGCAGGUAAAGAGGAGGAGGCUGUCUAGGUUCUACCAAAGCCAAAGAAUAAUAGUAAAAACAAAAAGCUACAAAAAAACCCAAUAGUCUCAUCUUUUGAUUUAUUUUUUGUUUGGCAGUCAUGGUAUAACUGAAAGCCAAGAAAAGGCCCUGCAUUUUUAAUGGAUUUACUCAACCAUUUCCUUUAAAAAAAAGUAAGAACAAACAAGCUCACAGGUUUUAUUCUUAUAAAAACACUGCAUGUUCAUUAUAGGAUGUUUUGAAAAUAAUGUUUACAAAAGUUCUGCCAUCCAGUUAACAGUUCUGCUGUACUUUGUGGUCCAGUUUUCCUCCCUAUUCUUUCUAUGUAAUUGAACCACAUACAUAUAAUUUUGUUUCCUGUGUUUUUGCACUUAACAAACGAACAAUAUGAAUUUUCCCCUCAUGUUAUUUAUAACUCUGUAUAAAUAUCAAUUUCACUGGUUCUCUAAAGUUCCAUUGUGUAAAUGUGCCAGGAUUUUCUUUACUCAUACUGUUGGAAAUUAGGAUGUUUCCAAUUUUUUUAAUUUAAAUUUACUUUUUGUCAUAAAUAAUGAUCCAGGGAAUAUUUUUAUGUUUUUUUCUUUAAUAUUUAUAAAAACAGCAUUAUUGGGUCAAGGAGUAUCGUUACUUUUCAGUUGCAUAUUGCCAAAUUAAUUUUUAUGGCUGUAUUAAGAUCCUUCAGCUGGGUGCGGUGGCUCACACCUGUAAUCCCAGCACUUUGGGAGGCUGAGUCAGGUGGAUCAUCUGAGGUCAGGAGUUUGACACCAGCCUGGCUAACGUGGUGAAACCCAUGUCUAUUAAAAAUACAAAAAUUAGCUGGGAGUGGUGGCAUGUACUUGUAUUUCCAGCUACAGGAGGCUGAGGCAGGAGAAUCGCUUGAACCCGGGAAGCAGAGGUUGCUGUGAGCUGAGAUUGCACUACUGCACUCCAGCCUGGGUGACAGACUGAGACUCUCAAAAAACUAAUAAUAAUAAAUUUUUUAAAAAAGACACUUUCAGGCAAUCAAUACAACCAUUUAGAAAAAUCUUUGCUGAUUUGACUUUUGGAAAAUCAUAGUGUUAAUAGUUUAAUUUGUAUAUCUCUGAUUCUUGUGAGGGUUAAUAUUUUUCCAUAAAUGUGUUGAGUGAAUUGGUUGUAUGUGUGGAAAAAUGUAAAUCUUUACCUACCUCACACAUAAAUCGUACUAGAUUUAAUCAAGGACUUAAAUAUGAAAACCAAAACUUCUUUACAGCAAAUACAGGAGGAUAUAUGAUCUCAAUGUCAGAUGAAUUUUUUUAAGACAAUAGAAGGGGCAGAUAGUAAAGGUAAACUGAUAAAUUUGACUAAAAUAAAAUGGAGAAACUUCUGAUCCUCAGGUACUAGAAAAAGAAUAAAAAGUCAAGAUACAAGGUCAAUGCAACAGUAAAGAAAAAGAAAAGACACAGGAUGAUCUGGAUGAACUGAUACAGAAUGAUUUCUAGGGGUCUGAAGUUUACCUGCCGUGUGAUAAAUUUUUUUGUUCUCUAUAUUUAGCCACACACUUCAAUCAUCGCUUUCCUGCAAUCGGGGAAAAAAAAAACUUUGCUUAAAAGCCAACCCAUCUUACAUUCCCACCAGCAGUGUAUAAGGUUUCUGGUUUCUCUGCAUCCCUCCCUUUGUCAUGAUAUUGUCAUGAUAGUGGUUGUGCAGUGGUAUCUUUUUGUGGCUUUAAUUUACAUUUUGAAUGACUAAUACUAUUAAGCACCUUUUCGUGUGCUUAUUAGCCAUUUGUGUGUUGUCUUUGGUCAAAGGUUUGUUCACAUCUUUUGCUCAUUUAAAAAAUUAGGUUUUAUUUAUAUCUUGGUAUCAUCUCUUGUCAGUUACGAUACACAGAUAUUCUAGCCUGUGGCUUAGAAGAUAUGAUACACAGAUAUUUUCUUCUAGCCUGUGGCUUAUCUUUCUUUUAAUGGUUUGUUUUGAAACACAAACACUUUUAAAUUUUAGUUAUUAAAUUUUAAUGAUGUUUAACUUAGCAGAGUUUUUCUCUUAUAUAUUGUGCUUUUGGUAUUGUGUCCAGGAACUCUUUGUCCAAACUAGAGUCACAAAGUUUUUUUAAAGAAGUUUUAUAGUUUCAUGGCCGAGCGCGGUGGCUCACGCCUGUAAUCCCAGCACUUUGGGAUGCCGAGGUGGGCGGAUCUGAAGGUCAGGAGUUCGAGACCAGUCUGGCCAACAUGGUGAAACCCAGUCUCUACUAAGAAAAUACAAAAAUUUGCCGGGCAUGGUGGCAUGCACCUGUAAUCCCAGCUAUUGGGGAGGCCGACGCAGGAGAAUUGUUUGAAGCCGGGAGGUGGGAGGUUGCAGUGAGCCGAGAUCGCGCCACUGCACUCCAACCUGAGCAACAGAGCAAGACGCCGUCUCAAAAAGAAAAAAAAAAAAGUUUUAUAGUUUUAGUUCAUACAUUUAGGUAUAUGACCCAUUUUGACUUAAUUCUUACCUAUGGUGUGAAGUAAGGGUUUACAUUUUUGUUUUUAGUUAUUCAUUUGUCCCAGCACCAUUUGUCAAGAAGACUUUCCUCAUUGACUCGUCUUGGGACGUUUCUUGAAAAUCAGUCGACUAUAAAUAAAAUGGCUCCAAAGGUUAAAUGAAGCAGGAAAAAUACAUAGAUGCAGCCUUGCAGCCUCUCCAGAUGUUUGGGGAUAAUAUUCCAGAUAGAAAUAUUGAUCCCUUGGAUUAGGUAACUAGUCAUAAUGAAGAAAAUUAGUCUUAAAACCUUACGGAAAUCUUUUAACUUGAAUAAAAGUAAAGAAGAAACUGAUUUCAUGGUAGUACAACAACCAUCGCUAGCCAGUGACUUUGGAAAAGAUGAUUCCUUAUUUGGUAGCUGCUAUGGUAAAGAUAUGGCCAGCUGCGAUAUCAACGGUGAAGAUGAAAAAGGCGGAAAAAACAGAUCAAAAAGCGAGAGCCUGAUGGGUACGCUAAAAAGGCGGCUUUCUGCAAAACAGAAGUCAAAAGGCAAGGCGGGCACACCCUCUGGGAGCUCUGCCGACGAGGACACCUUCUCCUCCUCCUCAGCACCCAUAGUCUUUAAAGACGUGAGAGCUCAGAGGCCGAUAAGGUCCACGUCGCUCCGCAGCCAUCACUACAGUCCCGCGCCGUGGCCUCUGCGGCCCACAAACUCCGAGGAGACCUGCAUCAAGAUGGAGGUGAGAGUCAAGGCCUUGGUUCACUCUUCCAGCCCGAGUCCAGCCCUGAAUGGCGUCCGGAAGGAUUUCCACGACCUCCAGUCUGAGACCACGUGCCAGGAGCAAGCCAAUUCACUGAAGAGCUCGGCUUCUCAUAAUGGAGACCUGCAUCUUCACCUGGAUGAACAUGUGCCUGUCGUUAUUGGACUUAUGCCUCAGGACUACAUUCAGUAUACUGUGCCUUUAGAUGAGGGGAUGUAUCCUUUGGAAGGAUCACGGAGCUAUUGUCUGGACAGCUCUUCUCCCAUGGAAGUCUCUGCGGUUCCUCCUCAAGUGGGAGGGCGCGCUUUCCCCGAGGAUGAGAGUCAGGUAGACCAGGACCUAGUUGUCGCCCCAGAGAUCUUCGUGGAUCAGUCCGUGAAUGGCUUGUUGAUUGGCACCACGGGAGUCAUGUUGCAGAGCCCGAGAGCGGGUCACGAUGAUGUCCCUCCACUCUCACCAUUGCUACCUCCAAUGCAGAAUAAUCAAAUCCAAAGGAACUUCAGUGGACUCACUGGCACAGAAGCCCACGUGGCUGAAAGUAUGCGCUGUCAUUUGAAUUUUGAUCCGAACUCUGCUCCUGGGGUUGCAAGAGUUUAUGACUCAGUGCAAAGUAGUGGUCCCAUGGUUGUGACAAGCCUUACAGAGGAGCUGAAAAAACUUGCAAAGCAAGGAUGGUACUGGGGACCAAUCACACGUUGGGAGGCAGAAGGGAAGCUAGCAAACGUGCCAGAUGGUUCUUUUCUUGUUCGGGACAGUUCUGACGACCGUUACCUUUUAAGCUUGAGCUUUCGCUCCCAUGGUAAAACACUUCACACUAGAAUUGAGCACUCAAAUGGUAGGUUUAGCUUUUAUGAACAGCCAGAUGUGGAAGGACAUACGUCCAUAGUUGAUCUAAUUGAGCAUUCAAUCAGGGACUCUGAAAAUGGAGCUUUUUGUUAUUCAAGGUCUCGGCUGCCUGGAUCUGCAACUUACCCCGUCAGACUGACCAACCCAGUGUCCCGGUUCAUGCAGGUGCGCUCGUUGCAGUACCUGUGUCGUUUUGUUAUACGUCAGUAUACCAGAAUAGACUUAAUUCAGAAACUGCCUUUGCCAAACAAAAUGAAGGAUUAUUUACAGGAGAAGCACUACUGAAAGAUUGAGAACCCUGCAUCUUGCACUUUGGGAAUAAGAACAAGAGAUUGAAAUACAGUUUACAAACUUUCAUUGCCAUCAAAAUCUUUUGCUGCCAUAACUAUUUCAGUUUUAUGUGUAAAAGAGUCAUCAGUUUGUUUAGGGGUGGGGAAGUGUCAGCAAGGUGUCUUGGGUUUAUUUUGGUUCUUUAAAAAAGGGAAGUCUUGAGGUUUUAGAGGUGUGAAUUAUGUUUCAUCAAUGUGCAGAAUAAUCACAAUGUGAAUUAUCAAAUUCUCCUCAAUGCCCCCCCCGCCCAGUCCUUUGCUGCUAUCCACUGUGAUUUUUAUGCAUUAAAAGCACAUUUCAUGUGUAUUCAACCCUAAGUAAAGUUGAAUGAAACUUAACAGAAUGGAAAUUGCUAUGUCUUUUUAAAUGGUCCAUUUUCAAAAGACAGUGUUGAAUAAACAUACCUGUGUGAUAAAACACAGAAUUUACAUAUACACUGAAGAUGAGUUUUUAAUCUCUUACUUUAAAAAGAUUUAUUUAGAAUCGUGAAUUGACAUAAUCUUGGGUAAUGGAACGGAGAUCUGCAACAUAUCUUUUAACAACACUUUUUUCUAAAUUAUUUCUAAGGUUGUGCUAAUUCUUUUGGUUGUGAAAAGUUGAAUUUUUCUGUUGCCUUCGUUUUCAUCUUCUAGUUUGUCUAUUUUAAUAAAUGGCCUUACAUUAAAAAAUUGUAAAGAAAUGUAUACCACCAAUUUAGAAAUUGUUGCCUUUUCUGUAAUUAAACUCGGGUACAAAUUGGCAUAACAUGAAAACCUAUGGAACUAGAAUUAUUAUUAAAGAAAUAUUAGAUGAUCAUAGCUUCCUGUGAUAGCAUUUUUUUGUGUGUUACCUAUCCUUUUGGUAAAAUGUUUUAUCUGUGAUUUCUUUAGCUUAGUCAACAUUUUCUUGGGUGAACUUGAUUGUCAACUAAUUUUCAUAAAUGGACUGGAUUCUCUUGCAACAUUAAUGUUUAUAAAAAGUUUUAAAUUGAUUUGAAUAGAAAGAAAACAUUGUUUUAAAGUUGGAUUUAUAUUUUUCUUCUAUGUAGUUACUAUAAAAGUGUGCUGGAUUUGACCAAUCCUUACCCCCACUAUAAAGAGAACCCGUGAUGACUUUAGUUUAAAAAUUGUGGAAAUUGUGGAGCAAUUUUUCUCACAAUGUGAGAAAAAUUCUAAACCAUAUUAGAUAAUGUGGAAGUCAUAUUGUCUAUCAUAUAUACUGCCAUUUAAAAAUAGGUUUUUAAAAUUUAGCUAAGUCUUAAGUAAUUUGCCGUUGCUAAUAAUUUUAUCUCCUUGAGUCGGUUGUUGGGGAGAGAUGUUAUAUUCAAUAAUUUUUAGUUAUUUUGUAAUGCAGAGUGUUUAUUCAUUUCACAGUUCUGCAAUGGAUGUAGUAUUUUGGGAUUGCCCUGUCCAGAAAAUUUUCAGCUACACACCUUUAAAGGAAAAUGUUUCUAUCUCAGAUGAAACAUGUAAUUUGGGAUGGUUCUUCCUUUGUCACUUAAAGGAAGAGAUAGGAAAAGUCUCUUACCCACUUUAAACAUGAGGGUAAAGGUUUAGGUCAAACUUACUGGCUUUGUCAUUCAAGCAUAUCUGAAUCCUCACUUUUUUCUCUUUGCUUUUUAGGGUCAGAACUGAGAUAUUACCAAGAAAAGGCACAAUGCCAUAAUAUUAUGGUGUUAUGGUAUUUUGACUUAAAGGGGAAAAGGUACUUAAUUUUGGUGGGAUGUUGAUUGUACCUUGUUAAAAAGACUCUCAUUUUCUCAUAUGUUUUCUCCUAAUAAGAUGGAAUAUGGAGUAUACUGUAAUAAUAUAAGUGUUCAUUAUAAGCUAUUUGGAUUAAGAACUAUUGCAGAGUUGUAAGCUUGUUAUCAAAUUAAUGCAAGACAUUUAAACUAUUUUUUUGCAAAACUAUUUAUUUUUAAAACAACUUAAAGUAUAUCUAGGGUGAGUUAAAAGUCCCUGUGCAUCUAUAUUAGAUGGCAGGUUUUGUCACAGAGUCACUGUGUAUUAAUAAUAAAUGUUGAAAUGGCUUCUCCGUGUCUCCAGAAGCAUUUACAUGUCCUCCUUGUGAGAUCAUGGUGCACAGAGGUCUUUGGACUGCCCUGAACCCGUCUUAUGUGGACAUAACCUAUUCCCUUCGUUUUCUCAUCAUGCCAUGUGUUUAAGAUCUACCCGCUUAGUGUCAAGAUUAUUGAGAUUUUCAUCUAAAUGUUUUUAAAAUUGUAUUUUGUGUUUUAGUGGAGGACAGUCUUGAUACUGUUCUAAUUCAGAAAGCCAAAUUUUGAUGCGCUUUUGUAUAUUCAUAAUAUAUACUUUAAUAUGCCCUAUUCUAAUCUAGUUUGAAAUUGUUAGAUUCUGAUAGUAUAAUGAUAAAAUCAAACUAUUUGCCAAAAAGUUAAAUUUACAAGCAGAAAGAUGUUUUGCGAUAUUUUCUACUUUUGUGUAGAAAGAUAACCAUUUGGGGUAGGCAGCACAACAGAAUGUGAAAGAUUGGCUUUAUAUGAUACUAACACAGUCCAGUUAAAAGUGGAAACAGGGAAAAGAGAGAGAGAAAACUCAUCAUUUAGUUUGGUCUAGACACAAUUUGGUUAAAUUUUAGGAUUCUAUUGGCAGUUAACAUAGAUGACAUGGACACAGCCUAUGAGUGCUUUUUAAAUACGUGCUUCUAAAAAUCUGAGCUCAAAGCAAGAAAAAGAAAACAGGAAAGCUGUAUCCAUUUGCCAUAAUAGAUGAAUCAGAAUUGUUUUCUAUUAAAUAUUUCAUCACGAAAUAUGAUGGAGGCCAGAAGCUAUUUUUAGGCUUACUAUAACACUAUUAUGCAUUUUUAUAAAUAAGAAGAAGGCUGUAGAAAGUACUUGAAAAAUAUCUAAUUCUCUUUCUGUCUAAGGAAAACUCUUUCUACUUGGUGCAAUAAUCUGAAAAUUUAGAAGGUCAAAAUAUGUCACAGGAAAUGAUCAUAGACCUAAAAAUAGUUUUUAAGGAAACCAGCUACACGGGGCAACCAACCAUCUUGCUGUUGAAGAAAACAGUUCCAAAAGGCUAAAUCAUUGGCAUAAAGGAAACAAAACCCAAAGUAUGCGUUGUAAUUCUUGAGCCAGUAUUACUGAAACAGGAUAAAAGUUAUAAAAUCUAACAUAGGUUAAUGCAAUGUCUCUGCUAGUGCUACAAGUCUAAAAUAUCUUUGUAACAAUGCUUUCAGAAAUGCCAGUUUUAAUUACAUUUCACAUUGUAUAUGAGAGAUACUGCUUUAUGAAUGAAUCGGAAUAAUACAUUUUCAUUUAAAUCUUAAUUGCUUUUCAUUAAAUGCGAAGUCUUAAUUUCAAAAUGAAAUCACACUACCAGCAAUAGACAGUUUUCUUGAAAACUCUAAUAAGGAACAAUAGCCAGUUCCGUAAAUAACUUUAAAAUUCUAAAAGUGUUGGUACACUAGCAAUCACAAAUAUGGUUUCUUUUAAUACUUUUUUAAUCCUGUAAAGAAGGGUUUUUAUAAACAUUCUUUUUAUUAAUCAGUCAUAACAUGGCGAAGUGUGUAGUUGCUGUUUCUGAAAAGUGAUCCAAACUCUACAUCCAGAGAUUAUGAAAAAUUCUUAUAGAAUUUUGUAACAAGUAUUUACAUGUUGGGUGAAAGAAAUUUCAUAGUCGUUGGAGUGCCAUGAAAUUAAUACUUGCAAUUCAGAUUGCGGUAGUUUACACUUUUUCUGUAUGUUUCAAAUCAGGUGUGUACCAUUUGUACUGAGAACACCACAGAAUGAAUUAUCCAAAGUCCAUUGAUUUUAAUACGUGUUUUGGUUUGUAAACAAAUUAUAGUAAUUUCUUGCACAUUUUUGGAAAUUAAUUGUAUAAGAAUUUAUGUAUCUGCUUCUAGAUACAGUGUGUAAAUAAAAAAUUUCGUUCACAAGA